AGCUUUGCAGUCGCUGCCUUCUCGCGCCUGACCAUGCACCCCUGCAUCUUCCUGCUGGGCCACAGGCGAGCGCUUUAUUUCUGGAGCUGAGGGCUAAAACUUUUUUGACUUUUCUUCUCCUCAACAUCUGAAUCAUGCCAUGUGCCCAGAGGAGCUGGCUUGCAAACCUUUCCGUGGUGGCUCAGCUCCUUAACUUUGGGGCGCUUUGCUAUGGGAGACAGCCUCAGCCAGGCCCGGUUCGCUUCCCGGACAGGAGGCAAGAGCAUUUUAUCAAGGGCCUGCCAGAAUACCACGUGGUGGGUCCAGUCCGAGUAGAUGCCAGUGGGCAUUUUUUGUCAUAUGGCUUGCACUAUCCCAUCACGAGCAGCAGGAGGAAGAGAGAUUUGGAUGGCUCAGAGGACUGGGUGUACUACAGAAUUUCUCACGAGGAGAAGGACCUGUUUUUUAACUUGACGGUCAAUCAAGGAUUUCUUUCCAAUAGCUACAUCAUGGAGAAGAGAUAUGGGAACCUCUCCCAUGUUAAGAUGAUGGCUUCCUCUGCCCCCCUCUGCCAUCUCAGUGGCACGGUUCUACAGCAGGGCACCAGAGUUGGGACGGCAGCCCUCAGUGCCUGCCAUGGACUG